GGACUGCCAGCAUGCUGUCACCUCUCAAUGUCAGCUGAGGAGAGGAAAGGAUUCUUAGCUUGAGUUCACUCCAGUUGCCUAAUGUCAUGCCCAUUGCUCAAGCCCAUGUGGCCUGUUUGAAGGAGAACUGCUUAUCUGUGCAGCAAUCUAUCCGAGGGCCUUUGGGCCAUUAUGCUGUGAAUGUGACAUCUGCAGCCAAGCUCUGCAGUCAGAGUCUAUGUAACAAUCAUGGAAGAGUAUUCGAAAAACACCUGAGUCCUCCUUCUAUCUGCAUAUGCCUGAAAGCAGUGUCAGGUCCCUCAGCUGCAGGUCUGUUGGAGUUUGCUGGAGGUCCAUUCCAGACCUUGUUUACCUGGGUAUCACCAGCGGAGGCUGCAGAACCGCAAGUAUUGCAGAAGAGCAAAUAUUGCUGAACAACAAAUAUUGCUGCCUGAUCCUUUCUCUGGAAGCUUCGUCCCAGAGGGCAGCCGCCUAUAUGAGUUGUCUGUCCACCUCUACUGGGAGGUGUCUCCCAGAUAGGCUACACGGGCAUCAGGGACUCACUUGAGGAGGCAAUCUGUCCUUUCUCAGAGCUCAAACGCGGUGCUGGGAGAACCACUGCUCUCUUCAGAGCUGUCAGACAGAGACGUUUAAGUCUGCAGAAGUUGUCUGCUGCCUUUUUUUGAGCUAUGUCCUGCCCACAGAGAUGGAGUCUAGAGGCAGUAGGCCUUGUUGAGCUGUGGUGGGCUCCACCCAGUUCGAGUUUCCUAGCUGCUUUGUUUACCUACUCAAGCCUCAGCAAUGGCGGACACCCCUCCCUCAGCCAGGCUGCUGCCUCACAGUUCAAUCUCAGACUGCUGUGCUAGGAGUGAGCAAGGCUCUGUGGGCGUGGGACCCACCGAGCCAGGCACGGGAAUCACCUUGUCUACUGGUUGCUAAGUCCUUGGGAAAAGCACUAUUUUGGUGGGAGUGUCCUGUUUUUCCAGGUAGUCUGUCACGGCUUACCUUAGCUAGGAAAGGGAAAUCCCCCAAUCUCUUACACUUCCUGGGUGAGGCGAUGCCCCCGCCUGCUUCAGCUCGCCCUCCUUGGACUGCACCCACUGUCCAACCAGUCCCAGUGAGAUGAACCAGGUACCUCAGUUGGAAAUGCAGAAAUCACCCGUCUUCUGCGUCGAUCAUGCUGGGAGUUGCAGACUGGAGCUGUUCCUAUUUGGCCAUCUUCCAGUUUCAAUAGUUCUUUAUUUUAUUUAUGCUAUCUAUUUCUUUUCCUUUUUUUUUUUUUUUUUUUUUUUUGAGAUGAAGUCUUACUCUGUUGCCCAGGCUAGAGUGUAGUGGUGUGAUCUCGGCUCACUGCAACCACUGCCUCCUGGGUUCAAGUGAUUCUCCUGACUUAACCUCCUGAGUAGCUGGGACUACAAGAGCAUGCCAUCAUGCCCAGCUAAUUUUUGUAUUUUUAGUAGAGAUGGGGUUUCACCAUAUUGGCCAGAAUGGUUUUGCAUUCCUGACCUCAAGUGAUCUGCCUGCCUCAGCCUCCCAAAAUGUUGGGUUACAGGGGUGAGCCACCGUGCCUUGCUAUUUAUGCCAUCUAUUUCACUGAAGAUUCCGCCUCUCAUUUCUUGAGUCAUUUUUUUUAAAUUUCCUUAAAUUGGACUUCACAUUUUUCUGAUGCCUCCUUGUUUAGCUUAAUAACUGACCUUCUGAAUUCUUUUUUAGGAAAAUCAGGAAUUUCUUCUUGGUUUGGAGCCAUUGCUGGACAUCCUUUGCCAUUCAACCUCUGAUUUGCACAAGGUGACUAAAGGACCAGCAGCAAACAAAAGCAAAGGUCUUCUAGAGUGCACUAAAGCAGAAGAUAACGUAACAUUUUUAUCUUACCAUGAAAGUAUUAUCUGAAGGACAGUUAAAGCUUUGUGUUGUUCAACCAGUACAUCUCACUUCAUGGCUCCUUAUAUUUUUUAUUCUAAAGUCUAUCUCUUGUCUAAAACCUGCUCGACUUCCAAUUUAUCAAAGGAAACCUUUUAUAGCUGCUUGGAAUGCUCCAACAGAUCAGUGUUUGAUAAAAUAUAAUUUAAGACUAAAUUUGAAAAUGUUUCCUGUGAUUGGAAGCCCACUGGCCAAGGCCAGGGGGCAAAAUGUCACUAUAUUUUAUGUCAACAGAUUGGGAUACUAUCCGUGGUAUACAUCACAAGGGGUCCCCAUUAAUGGAGGUCUCCCACAGAACAUAAGUUUACAAGUACAUCUGGAAAAAGCUGACCAAGAUAUUAAUUAUUACAUCCCUGCUGAAGAUUUCAGUGGACUUGCUGUUAUAGAUUGGGAAUAUUGGCGACCACAGUGGGCCCGGAACUGGAACUCAAAAGAUGUUUACAGACAGAAGUCAAGAAAGCUUAUUUCCGAUAUGGGAAAGAAUGUAUCAGCUACCGAUAUUGAAUAUUUAGCCAAAGUGACCUUUGAAGAAAGUGCAAAAGCUUUCAUGAAGGAAACCAUCAAAUUGGGAAUUAAGAGCCGACCCAAAGGCCUUUGGGGUUAUUAUUUAUAUCCUGAUUGCCACAAUUAUAACGUUUAUGCCCCAAACUACUCUGGGUCAUGCCCAGAAGACGAAGUCUUGAGGAACAAUGAGCUCUCUUGGCUCUGGAACAGCAGUGCUGCUUUAUAUCCUUCUAUCGGUGUCUGGAAAUCCCUUGGAGACAGUGAAAACAUUUUGCGCUUCUCCAAAUUUCGGGUGCAUGAAUCCAUGAGGAUCUCCACCAUGACAUCUCAUGAUUAUGCUCUGCCUGUAUUUGUCUACACAAGGCUAGGGUACAGAGAUGAACCUUUAUUUUUCCUUUCUAAGCAAGAUCUAGUCAGCACCAUAGGAGAAAGUGCUGCCUUGGGAGCUGCAGGCAUUGUUAUUUGGGGAGACAUGAAUUUAACUGCAUCCAAGGCCAACUGUACAAAGGUGAAGCAGUUUGUGAGUUCUGAUUUAGGGAGCUACAUAGCCAAUGUGACCAGAGCUGCUGAGGUAUGCAGCCUUCACCUCUGCAGGAACAAUGGCAGGUGCAUAAGGAAGAUGUGGAACGCGCCCAGUUACCUUCACUUGAACCCUGCAAGUUACCACAUAGAGGCCUCUGAGGACGGGGAGUUUACUGUGAAAGGAAAAGCAUCUGAUACAGACCUGGCAGUGAUGGCAGAUACAUUUUCCUGUCAUUGUUAUCAGGGAUAUGAAGGAGCUGAUUGCAGAGAAAUAAAGACGGCUGAUGGCUGCUCUGGGGUUUCCCCUUCUCCUGGUUCACUAAUGACACUUUGUCUACUGCUUUUAGCAAGUUAUCGAAGCAUUCAGUUGUGAGAUAAUUGAGUUUAAAGGGAAUUGUGUGGCCUCUAGCCUAGUCAUUUAAAGAAGGAUGUAACUUAUAACAUUUUUUUUCUCUUAUGAAUUCUAUUGAGAGAUAUUAUAAGUAGACAUUAUGUAUGUCACUUAACAUAAACAGAAACAUUAUUUUAUUUGCCUCCAGUCUGGCUAGGAAACCAGAUCUGGGGUAAAGUCAAUGUACACUUCCUCCUUAUUGGAAUAUUUAAGUUGCAUUUAAACUAAAACUAGUAUAAUUUAGUCUUUUCAUGAAUGUACAUACAUAAAAUUAUACAUAAAAAUAUUAAAUUAUUCAUUUCAAAGAC